GUUCCGGUUGCGGAUGGUGAGUGUGUCGGGGGGCUUGGCGGCUUUUCUCCUCAGUUUUCUGGAGUGCUUUGGAGGAGAGGACUAUGGCAGCCAGGGACGCCACUUCAGGCAGCCUGUCAGAGGAGAGCAGUGCUUUGGACCUGCCAUCAGCGUGUGACAUAAGAGAUUACGUCCUGCAGGGACCCAGCCAAGAAGCCAACAGCGAGGCUUUCAGUUCUUUGGAAUUCCAUUCUUUUCCUUAUUCUUCUGAUGUGGAUCCAGGCGUGAGCCACUGCAUCCAGCCUAAACUCACUAGGGAGAUUUUUUGAAUAGCCUGUACUCUGUAGCUAGUUUAGCUUGCUACCAAGGUUUAGCCUUUCUGGGUCUGUACUGAAUAUCCCAGGUAUUCAACAGUCAUCUCACUCUGGCUGUCAGAACAUGCAUGUCUCCCAGCCCUGUGUGAGUUCUGGAAGUUGUUCAGCUCACAGCUCCCCUGGCUGUGCCUGGCAUUAUGACUUAGUGUUCACUGUGAAAUACUCAAAAGAAUCCCUAUGCUGAUUUCUGGAGCUCUUUAUCUGUUUAGCUCCCUCAUCUCCAGGACUCAGCUUCAGAAAUUCCAGGCACCUGAAACUGAUCUCUGUCUCUUUGCUGAGGAAACUGCUGUGAGGCAGUGAGAUUGCUGUGCUCUGUUUGGAUUCCCCUUCCCUGCGCUGUGGUCUAGGAAGUGCCUCCAGCAGAACACUGGGGGCAAUUGUAGGCACAUCUUGCGUCCCUUCUCUCAGUGAUCAAAGUCCUAUACUAACUGUGACCAGGAUCUGAAAGCAGUUGUUUUUUGUCCAGUUUUCUUUUCUUUUUCUCCUUUUUUUCUUUUUCUUUCUUUUUUUUAUUUUUUUAUUUUUUUUGAGACAGCCUUGCUCUGUUGGAGUGCAGUAGCACUAUCUCGGCUCACUGCAACCUCUGCCUCCCAGGUUCAAGCGAUUCUCCUGCCUCAGCCUCCCAAGUAGCUGGGAUUACAGACACCUGCCACCACGCCUGGCUAAGUUUUGUAUUUUUAGUAGAGAUGGGGUUUCACCAUGUUGGCCAGGCUGCUCUAGAACACCUGACCUUAAGUGAUCCACCCGCCACAGCCUCCCAAAAUACUGGGAUUACAGGCGUGAGCCACUGCACCAGGCCAUUUUGUCCAGUUUUAUAGCCAUUUAUAGCAGAAGGGCAAAUUUGGUAUAGUUAACUCUGCCAUUGCCAGAGGCUGUUCACUUAGAUUUGUCUUGUAACAUUUUUCUGUAGUAAGUAAAGGCAGGGAUCCUGUACCCAUUUUAUAGGUUAAAUAAUGCAGAGUUGCCAAGAAAUAAGAGGGUUGGAAUCACAUACUGGGUUGGUUGGUAGGUAGGUCAUAUGAUCCAGGAACUCUUGGUCCUUGCAAGGAGAUAGGAGGAAAUGCUCAAAUUUGUCUCCCCAAAUGGGGGCCUGGGUUGAGGUUUAUAAGCAUAUGGUAAUGAGGCGUGAAUGAGGUGACUGGAUUGAUCUUGGAAUGAGGUGAUUGAUUGGAUCUUACAAUAAGGCGAUGAUGUUGGGGGUCAUGAUCUAACUGGAAUCCACCAUGGGGUGACUCCAGGGCUCAAUCUGAUUGGAUCCUGGAUCCUGCCAUGCAGUGUCCACUUCUGUUUUGUUUUGUUUUGUUGAGAUGGAGUCUUGCUCCAUUGUCCAGGCUGGAGUGCAGUGGCAUGAUCUCAGCUCACUGCAACCUCUGCCUCCUGGGUUCAAGCAAUUCUUGGGCCUCAGCCUCCCAAGUAGCUGGGACUACAGGUGUGCGCCAUCACACCCAGCUGAUUUUUGUGUUUUUAGUAGAAACAGGUUUCUCCAUGUUGGCCAGGCUGGUCUUGAACCCCUGACCUCAAGUGAUCUGCCCGCCUCAGCCUCCCAAAGUGCUGGGAUUACAAGUGUGAGCCACCGUGCCCCGCCAGUGUCUACUUCUUAAUUCAGUCCCACUCCUCGGUCUGAGCACUUAGGUUCCCCCUAGUGGAACUAAGCAUGGUUGCAUGCUUGGUUCAUCUGGGCAUGCUCAGGUUAUGAGACCUGAGGGUCCGUGACAACUGAAAAACAACUCACAACUUUGUUACGUAAAAGUUGAACCAGAUUGAUCUGGUGUGACCACACUCUUACCCUUAUCUGUUAUUUCUCAUUCCAAACUUUGCUUAUUAACUGUAAUGUUUGCCUUUGUAAUUGCUUCACUUUCAUCACAUAUAAGAAGUACUCAAUGAAUGCUUACUGAUUUCAUGCACUGUAGGAACAACACCGACUAUUGUCAUGUUGGCUGUUGUCAUAUUAAAACAUCAUGUAGGCCAGUCAUGGUGGUUCACAUCUGUAAUCCCAGCACUUUGGGAGGCUGAGACAGGAGGAUCCUUUGAGGUCAGGAGUUCGAGACCAGCCUGGGCAACACAGCAAGACCCUGUUUCUACAAAAAAUAAAAAAAUUAGCCAGGCAUGGUGGAGUACACCUUUAGUCCUAGCUACUUGGGAGGUUGAGGCAGGAGGAUGGCUUGAGCCCAGGAAGCCAGGGCUGCAGUGAGCCAUGAUGGUGCAACUGCACUCCAGCCUGAAUGACAGCGUGAGACCCAGUCUCUUAAAAACAACAACAAUAAAAUCAUCAUGUAACUUGCUAAGACAGCCACACCUUUGUGUUGUGCCUAAAAAAUUACUGAGUUCUGGUGGAUACAUAAUGAGGACUUGACAGUGUUUUUUUUUUGUUUUUUGUUUUGUUUUUAGAAGGAGUCUUGCUCUGUCGCCCAGACAGGCUGGAGUGCAGUGCUGUGAUCUCAGCUCACUGCAACCUCCAUCUCCUGGGUUCAAGUGAUUAUCCCGCCUCAGCCUCCCCAGUAGCUGGGAUUACAGGCGUGUGCCACCAUGCCUGGCUGAUUUUUCUAUUUUUAGUAGAGACAAGGUUUCACCAUGUUGGUUGUCCAGGCUUGUCUCCUGACCUCAGGUGAUCCGCCCACCUCGGCCUCCCAAAGUGCUGGGAUUAUAGGCGUGAGCCACCAUGCCCAGCCAGUCUUAUUAAAUGCUUCAAAUAUAUGUCACAUUCAGCUUCAUGUCCCUGAUGGUUCCCUGCACCAUGCUACGCCAAUAAACACUCAACGGAUACUCAACGGAUACAAAAGAGUAUUUGGUAGAUCUUCAGAGACGGAAAGCAAAUUCAGUGCCUUUAUUCAGCAAAAAUUCAAUGAGCAGCUGCUAUGUGCUGGACACUGUGCUAGCCCCUGGGGAUGAAGUGUGAAUUAAAGGCAGUGUCUGCCCUCUUGAAGUUCACCACCCAGUGAUAGAACACCCAAGAAACCAGCCUCCAAGAUGUUCAGAUUAAAAGAAAUUCUUCCACAGUGACAUUUUCACCAGGCAAACUCAGAGUUGUUUGACAUGAGAAGGUUUAAAAAAGGAUAGUUGUGAAAGACCAGGCAAAGUUCACAAAGUGAAGAAGGGAAAAUAUUAUUUCAGACUGAUAUUAAAUGAUGGCCUAGCCUGCUGCCAUACUGUCUCACAGGGAAAAGUUUUAUUUAUGUCUCCUUUGAUCUUUUCUCCUUUUUGUCUCUAGGUUUGAUGUACAAGCUUUAGCUUGGGCCUUUGAUUUACAGUGUUCUGGAGAAAGAGACCAGGGAUGACAAAGCCAACCAGGCUGUUACCUAAAAACCUGAUAUAUUGUCCUAGAUCUAGGCUGUCUUAGAGCUACACAAAGAAUUUCCAGCAGACUGCUCAGGAAGAGCCUGCUGGGAAGGCAGUUCCCCUAAAGUCCCAUAAAAUAAAGAGCUUCCCAGUCCUUCUUUGAUAUCCACGGUUUGCUUAAGUAUUGGAUGUUAAGGCAGCAACUUCUAGUCCUGUGGAAAAUCUUUUAAUAUCUGUGCUUAAUCAACUGAGAAAAUAAAAAUUUAUAGAUCCAUCAAUGACAAAUAUAUUAAACAUGGGGCUUUAAAAAUUG